CUUGUGUUCUCGCGAGAGGCGGGAAAGGGCGCAGGGUUUGAAACAUGGCGGACGACGUAGACCAGCAACAAACUACCAACACUGUAGAGGAGCCCCUGGAUCUUAUCAGGCUCAGCCUAGAUGAGCGAAUUUAUGUGAAAAUGAGAAAUGACCGAGAGCUUCGAGGCAGAUUACAUGCUUAUGAUCAACAUUUAAAUAUGAUCUUGGGAGAUGUGGAAGAAACUGUGACUACUAUAGAAAUUGAUGAAGAAACAUAUGAAGAGAUAUAUAAAUCAACGAAACGGAAUAUUCCAAUGCUCUUUGUCCGGGGAGAUGGCGUUGUCCUGGUUGCCCCUCCACUGAGAGUUGGCUGAAACAAAGAAUUUGUCCUGUAUGGAAAACGGGAGACUUUGUACAGUGGCCUCUCUAAAAGUACAAAACAUUCAUAAGAGAAACCUGCAUACAUUUUGAUAUUAAGAAAUAAUUCCGGGGAUUCUUCCACUCCUGAAAUGAGUUGAUUUGCAGAUAACUCACAACUUCUUAAGCUAAAUGGUAUUUUCAUUUUUCUCAAGCUCUCCAAUAAAUAUGACCACCAAGAUGCAGAACUCUUUCAGGACUUCUUUUGCUCCAUUAUUCUCACAGAUACUUACUGAUUUUUCUUUUCUUUAAAUUGGUGUUUCCUUGUAGAUUUUUUUAAGUGCGGUCUUCUGUCUUGUGAAUUAUUUAAAGUAAGCAUGUCUUACCUUCACUUAGCACACAUUUGCAGUGCACCUACUGUGUUUGAGGCACCAGGUUUGAGUGCUGGGAACCAGAGUUUUAUCAAAAUGCUUUCUGGGCCAGACAUGGUGGCUCAUGCCUGUAAUCCCAGCACUUUGGGAGGCCAAGGUGGGUGGAUCACCUGAGGUCAGGCGUUUGAGACCAGCCUGGCCAACAUGGUGAAACCCUUUCUCUACUGAAAAUAUAAAAAUUAGCCAGGCGUGGUGGCGCAUACUUGUAAUCCCAGCUACUCAGGAGGCUGAGGCAGUAGACGCUUGAACCCAGGAGGCAGAGGUUGCAGUGAGCCAAGAUCACACCAUUGCACUUCAACCUGGUCAACAGAGCGAGACUCCGUGUCAAAAAAAAAAAAAAAAAAGUUUUCUGCCCUCAAGUCUUCUGGGGAGGCAGAUGUUUAAACCAACAAUUGCAGGCAGUAAGAUUAGUGCUGAUAGAAUCAUGCACAUGCAGGAUGCCAUAGGAGCAUGGGGAAGAGCACCCAAAUAUGGGAGAAAGGGGCAGAGGGACAUUGUAAACAUCAACCCUGCAGUAGAAGACAGAGCAAAGCAUGAUUUCUCUUUUCUCUGGCCUGAUUUAAUUCUAAGGUCAGACGUUCAGCUUGAUCAUAACCUGUUUAUAAUUAUGACUCAGACCAUUUUUCCACUCUUGGAUCAUUGGCCAUUAAUGAUGAGGGGUCUCAAACAACAUGUCUCAGUGACACAGUAAAGCAGAAAUUGGCUGAAAGCAAAGCUGUUUUUAUUUCUAGCUUCAGUCAGCACAUAAUGCUUAAAACCUAAAGAGGAAAGUAAAAGCGUGUUACAAUCUCUCAAACUUUAUCAAGACAGGGCUUAGAACCUGACAUCCUCCGCUAUGGUCAUUCCAUUUUGAAAUGUAGAAAAUCCAACUUGUGGAUGGUUUGUCUGUAAAUGAGCUGAAUGUGUGUGCGUGUUCAUUAUCAAGCACGAUAUGCUCACAAAUGCACAGUACUUUAAGCCUUGUGCAAGAAAGAUGCUUUCAGUAAACAUAUUUAAAAGGUUUUAUUUUCCUUACUAAUGGUACAUGCCCCUGCAAGUUCAUGGAGAAGAGAAAAACAAGUGUGGGUGAGCUGAUGGAGGCUUCAUCUUAGGUGAGGAGGCAGGAGAGACACCCUCCCUUCACUUGUGCCAUCCCCACGCUUUGUCCUUAAGCUGUAGUGGUCCCAGGAGAUAACCUGUUUACAGCAGCCCAUUCAGUAUUGAAAAAUGAACUCCCUCCUGCAGAAUGUUAGAAGAAACAACCUCAAAGACCUCAGGCCGCCUGUGGUCAUUAGUAUGUGGCAGCAAGAUUGAACCUGCCUGCCUCCUACCUGUGUGAGCCUGUGGUGUGGGUGUGGUACCAAGGCCCUGGCUCUGGGCAGUCUGUUGGCUCCUGGUGUUCACUAAGGCGUGGGGUGACAGGCCAUCUGGCCUCGCUCUGCCAGUCUGCAGUUCUCCCCAGCACUGCAUUCAUUUUUAGUGGUUUCUGAUAGUCACACUGAAUUCCUGGACACUUUCUUCUCUUCAUUCUUAGUUAUCUUUCUCCUUUUUCUCCUGGAACUGAUAGUUUACACUAAAACUUUUGGCUGUGAGGACUUGAUUAUACACAUUUCUAAAACCCAUGAACCUUAAUAUCUGACACUGUUACUCUCAUAUGCACACACAACUAAAACAUACCAACCUACUUCAUUUCCUAGCUGCUAAGAUACAAGGGGAGGGACAAUAAAAGGUUAACUGCAGAAUAGCCACCUAUGUGUCAGGAAAUGGAGGGAGGGGAGGCAAUGUGUGAGUCCUUUUGGAGCUGGGACUCAAUCCACAACAGAGACAGCUCAAGCAGGGCCCUGCCAUGGUCCACACUGAGGUUUCCUCUGCAGUGGUGCUGUCCACUGAGGGGUUAUGGUGUGAGGGCCCCUGGGAGCCACGCCUUGGACUUCUGAGUCUGCAGAGCACUCGGCUCCAGCCAGCUGGAUGGCAGGUGGUCAGUGGAGCUGGUGACUGGUGGUUUCUGCAAUGAGGUGUCAGAUUAGCCUAAGGGAAGCCUCUUCAGCAAGUAUCAUGCCUGGAUCCCGGUCUUGGUUGUUUUAUGAGAGGCCGAUAUGAAUUGCCAUUGCCUCCCACAAAGAAAAAUGGACAAAAUAUGGGACCACAUCUUUGAGAUGAAAUGUGCCCAAAAUGAAAAGUAACUUGAGUAUCCCAAGUUAAACUUAAUCAUUAGCUGCAAAUGGACGAUUUUCAAAUUUCAAAUAGUGAUUUUUGAAGAUUUGCCCAAACUAGAGUACUAUCCCUCUUCACACUAAGAGGCAGAAAGUGGUUUCACACACCCUUUUAUUUAAUCAGCUAAAGUGGGUGCGGUGACACACACCUGUAAACUCAACCACUAAGGAGACUGAGGCGGGAGGAUUACUUGAGCCCAGGAGUUCGAGAUCAGCCUGAGCAACAUAACAAGACCCUGUCUCAAAUAAUACUUAGCUAUUACCCAUAUUGCUUUUAGCCUGCUGCCAGGAGGGGAGAAAUGUUAUUGUUUGAACAGAUGUCAGAUGUGAGUAAUGCUCAGCUGUGUUCAAUGUAGAAAAUUAAUAAAAGUUCCAGGAGUCAUCCUGGCUAGAUCAAGAA